AAGCUUUCCCCGGUGUCGGCGGCAGGUGGAAUUUCCACGCUUUAUCUGCGCCUGCGCCGCGCGGGAUUCGCGGUCCGAGCUGAAGAGGUUCGCGGUCCGGGUAACUGAUUGGUUUUCCUGGGGCUUGUUCUGCCUGGUUUUGCAACCCCUUUGCUUUUUGGGUUUCACUUCUCCGAACCCUGAGGCAGUGUGUGAAGCUGGGACGCCAGCCAUGUUCCAGACCGCUUGGCGCCAGAGACAAGGUUGCCUAGGCUCUUCUCAAACUCCUAGAUGCAAGCCAUCCUCCCGCCUCCACCUCCCAAAGUGCUGGGAUUACAGGCAUGAGCCACCAUGCCUGGCCUUACAGUUUUCUUUGGCUAAUGUUGUCAUGGAACCAGUGACCUUUGAGGAUGUGGCUGUGUACUUCACCCAGAAUGAAUGGGCCAGCCUGGACUCUGUGCAGAGGGCCCUGUACAGGGAAGUGAUGCUGGAGAAUUAUGCAAAUGUGGCUUCCCUGGCAUUCCCAUUCACCACGCCUGUUCUGGUCUCCCAGCUGGAGCAAGGGGAACUGCCAUGGGGCCUCGAUCCCUGGGAACCUAUGGGCAGGGAGGCUCUCAGAGGUAUCUGUCCAGGGGAUGAGGCCAGAACUGAGAAGGAAGGAUUAACUCCAAAGGAUCAUGUGUCCAAAGAAACAGAGUCCUUCAGACUGAUGGUGGGGGGCCUGCCAGGGAAUGUUUCCCAGCACCUUGACUUUGGGAGCAGCCUAGAGCAGCCACAAGGUCAUUGGAUAAUUAAGACAAAGUCAAAGAGGAGACAUUUCACAGAUACCUCAGCCAGGCACCAUGAGGCCUAUGAGGUCAAGAAUGGAGAGAAGUUUGAGAAAUUAGGAAAAAAUAUUAGCGUCAGCACACAACUCACUACAAAUCAGACAAAUCCUAGUGGUCAGAUAUCUUAUGAAUGUGGACAAUGUGGCAGAUAUUUCAUUCAAAUGGCAGACUUCCACCGACAUGAGAAAUGUCACACUGGUGAAAAGUCUUUUGAAUGCAAAGAAUGUGGAAAAUACUUCAGAUAUAACUCAUUACUUAUUCGGCAUCAGAUAAUUCACACUGGAAAGAAACCAUUUAAAUGUAAAGAAUGUGGAAAAGGUUUAAGUUCAGACACAGCCUUGAUUCAGCAUCAGAGAAUCCACACUGGAGAAAAGCCCUAUGAAUGUAAGGAGUGCGGCAAGGCCUUCAGUAGCAGCUCUGUCUUCCUCCAGCACCAGAGGUUCCACACUGGGGAGAAGCUCUAUGAAUGUAACGAAUGUUGGAAAACUUUCAGUUGCAGCUCAAGUUUCACUGUCCAUCAGCGAAUGCACACUGGGGAGAAACCUUAUGAAUGUAAAGAGUGUGGAAAACGAUUAAGCUCCAACACAGCCUUGACUCAGCAUCAGCGAAUUCACACUGGGGAGAAGCCCUUUGAAUGUAAGGAGUGUGGGAAGGCAUUCAAUCAGAAAAUAACCCUGAUUCAGCACCAGCGAGUUCACACUGGCGAGAAACCUUAUGAGUGUAAAGUGUGUGGUAAAACCUUCAGCUGGUGUGGAAGAUUCAUUCUGCAUCAGAAACUACACACUCAGAAGACACCUGUCCAAGCAUAGGGCUAUCCAUAGUUAGGCCCACUGUGCCUCUCCUUUUUUCUCUUUAUUUUCAUGCUUUUUAUCAGUGUCCUCGCUGUCCUUCCUGGUUAGACACUUGGCUUUCAUCAUGAACUCUUCUUUAAGUUUUUUGAACCUGUUUCCCCAACAUGAAGUCUCUUUAUGGUUAGAGAAGACCAAAAAACAAACAAACAAACUUAGAAACAUAAAAGGAAAUGUAAGUUUCCAGAUUUAAAGGACAUGCUGGGUGCCCAGCAGGAUGGAUUCAAGGGAAACCUACAUUAAGGAAAAUUGCUGUGAAUUAUGAAAACACCAAGUUUGAAUAAGAGGAUCAUGGAGAAAAAAUGAGACCCUAAAAAGUUUCUAGAGAGAGAAAACAAAAGAUCAGAAAUGAAAGCGGGGCCAGGCGCGGUGGCUCGUGCCUGUAAUCCCAGCACUUUGGGAGGCUGAGGCGGGUGGAUCAUGAGGUCAGGAGUUCGAGACCAGCCCGCCCAAUAUGGUGAAACCCCGUCUCUCCUGAAAAAAAAAAACACAAAAAUUAGCCAGGCAUGGUGGCGCAUGCCUGUAAUCCCAGCUACUAGAGAGGCUGAGGCAGGAGAAUCACUUGAAUCCCUGAGGCAGAGGUUGCAGUGAGCUGAGAUCGCACCACUGCACUCCAGCCUGGGCGACAGAGUGAGACUUUGUCUCAAAAACAGUAAAAAAUGAAAAUGGCAUUAGAUUUUUCAAGAGCAACCUUCAAAGUCAGAUGACAAUGUGUAUGCCUUCAGACUUCUCAUGGAAAAUGUUUUCCCCUGCAAUUCUAUACUCCAAAGUAUAAGUAUAGAAUAAAGGCAUUUCAGACCCUUUAAAUCUGAAAUCUUUAUCUCCCAUGCAUCCUUUCUCAUAUGUGCAACACUACACAAGGAGUAAACCAGUAAAUAAAAAGACAGAUAUAUGGAUUCCCUAUUGCAGUCCGUACGUCAGAAGUCUCCUAAAUUCAAAAACGGGCCCUGUCCAUGUGGAGCCAAAUGCAUCUUGGAAGACAUUCCUAGUAGGGUGCAAACUUCCAGAGACCUAUCUCAGGUUCAGUGUCCACCCACCCUACUUAUUCUUCAGUUUGUCUUCACUAGACAGUUGUACUCUGUGCCUUUGCAAAAGUCAGGAUGUAUAUACUCUUUGAGUCAGGUGCAAGGCACCAUUUGUCUUAAAUUUAUUCUCAUUGCUGUUUCAAGUGACCUCAAAGCAGGCAGCAUUUUCUUGCAAUUCCAUCUAGUUAUUUUUUAUGAUCAUGGAAGAACCUACCAUUAUUGCUGUUACCUGUGGAAAUGAGGGAAGAUGUAAAUGUGUUAGGUUUUAGCAUCCCCUCUGGCAGCCAGCUUGAUUUUGCAGGAAGCAGAGAGUAGUGAUUAAUAAUACAGAGCCAGGCAGACUUUGGUUUGAGUCCAGGUGUUUGUCCUUGGUUAAGUUACAAAAACUGCACUAGUUUCCUUAUCUGUAAAAUGAGGAUGACAGUUAAUCUACCUCAUAGGUUUGUGUUGGGGAUUAAAUGCAUUAUUUGUAGAAGUGUUUCAAACAGUGACUACAUAUAAUAAAAGUAUUACCUAUUAUUGGCCGGGCACAGUGGCUCAUGCCUGUAAUCCCAGCACUUUGGGAGGCUGAGGUGGGCAGAUCACAAGGUCAGGAGAUCAAGACCAUCCUGCUAACACACUGAAACCCUGUCUCUACUAAAAGUACAAAAAAUUAGCUGGGCGUGGGGUGACAUGUGCCUGUAGUCCCAGCUACUUGGGAGGCUGAGGCAGGAGCCCAGGGAGGCAGAGGUUGCAGUGAGCCAAGAUCAUGCCACUGCACUCCAGUCUGGGUGACAGAUUGAGACUCCGUCUCAAAAAAAAAAAAAAAA